UAUUCGUGUGCUUAUUUACUAUUUUUAUAUGUUCUUAGUCAGCUUGUGUGUUCCAAGUUUUUUUUUUUUACCAUUUUCGUAUUUGGUUGUCUUAUUAUUGAAUUGUAAUAAUUACCUGCCUGUUCUAGGGUAUCAUUUGCUGUCUGGAUACAUAUAUAUUGAAUAUUUUCUUCAUUUUUAUGGCUUGUCUUUUCAUUUCUUUAUGGUGUCUUUUGAAGAGCAAUUUUAAAGUUUGAUUACGUUUCAGAUAUAUCAACUAUUAUAUGGUUCAGGCUUUUUGUGUCUUAUCUAAGAAAUAUUUGUCUACCCCUAAGGUCCUGAAGACUUUGUCCUAUAUUUUGUUCUGGAAGCUUUGACAUUUUACAUUGAGUCAGUGAUCCAUUUGAGUUAGUUUUUUUCCUCAUAGACAGUCGAUUAUUCCAGUCUUGUUUGUUGAAAAGACUGUCCUUUCUCUACAAAAUUGCCUUGGCACCUUGGUUGAAAAUUAACUGUUCUCUCUUCCUGUUUACUAGAAGAAUUUUUAAAAGACCGGUGUUAUUUUUUUCCUUAAGGGAUUGGUAGAAUUCACAUAUGAACUAUUUCUAGGCUUUGACUUUUCUUUUUGGGGUUUUAGUAGUGAAUUCAUUUGCUUUAGUAGAAAUAGGUACUUCAGAUUUUCUUUUUUGUCUUGUGUCAGUUUUUUCAAAGUUGUGUUUUUUCAAAGAAUUUGUUUACUUCUAAAUUGUCAAAUUUGUUUGCAUGAAUUCUUAUUACCCACUUAAUGUCUAUAGGGUGUGUAGUGUGUACUUCCUAAUAUUGGUGAUUUGCUUUCUCUCUUUCACUUGGUUCACAUAGCUAUAGAUUUAUCAAUUUGAUCUUUUCAAGAAACAGCUUUUGGUUUUAAUUUGUAUUGUUUGUUUUCAAUUUUAUUAGUUUCUUUUCUGAUAUUUAUUAUUCCCUUUCUAUUUUGGGUUUACUUUACCUUUUUCUAGCUUUUUAGGGUGGAGUUUAUGCCAUUCAUAUUAGACCUUUUCUAAUAAAAAUAUCUUAAGACUAUAAAUUUUCUUUCAAAAUCACCUUUAGCUGCAUACUACAAAUUUUGACUUUUAAAAUUUUUCAUUUAGUUAAGAAUGUUUUCUGAUUUCCCUUUUGAUUUCUUCUUUUACCCAUAUUUUAUUUAAAAGUGUAUUUUAAUUUUCAAAUAGCUAUUCAGGUGAUAAUUUCAUCUAUAGCACUAAAAACCAAUGAAAAUUCUGACAUAUAUUUGUUUAUAAAAUUCCUUGAAUGCUCUGUAUAUUGUAUUUAUAUGGUAUAUACCUGAGGGCUUUUCUGUAGCAUAAAAGAACAGUUCAUUAUUUUUCACUGUUCUCUGGGUUGAAGGAGCUCAUUUGGGCAGCUCCAUCUUGGGGGUCUCUCUCUUGUAGUUGCAGUCAGAUGGCAGCUGGAAUGAGAGUCAUCUGAAGGCUUGACUGGGCUGGAUGGUCAAGAUAGCCUCUUCACUCACUCUGCUAGAAUGACUGGGACAGCUGGGUGUGGGCUGGUCACCUCUCUCCGCACAGCUUCUUCAUGGGACUAGUUGGCUUUCACACAACGGGGCAGUCUGAAGGCAGUCAGAUUUCCUACAUGACAGCUGACUUCUAGAGUGAGCAUUCUAAGACAUUGAGUUUUUUCAAGUAGAUAAUUUAUUUGCUCUACUCUUUCAAACUAAGAAGUAAGAUAAAUGUAUGGGGCCAGUCAUUGUAGAAACUGCCUGUCUGGCUCUUGCUGAUUGAAUUCCUUUGGUGCAGUUUAGCAUGUUCCUCUGUGUUCUGCAUCUCCUGUAGUGUAAUGUUCAAGCUCAGAAAUGCCUUAUGUGGAUCGUCAGAAUCGCAUUUGUGGUUUUCUAGACAUUGAAGAAAAUGAAAACAGUGGGAAAUUUCUUCGAAGGUACUUCAUACUGGAUACCAGAGAAGAUAGUUUCGUGUGGUACAUGGAUAAUCCACAGAACCUACCUUCUGGAUCAUCACGUGUUGGAGCCAUUAAGCUUACCUACAUUUCAAAGGUUAGCGAUGCUACUAAGCUAAGGCCAAAGGCGGAGUUCUGUUUUGUUAUGAAUGCAGGAAUGAGGAAGUACUUCCUACAAGCCAAUGAUCAGCAGGACCUAGUGGAAUGGGUAAAUGUGUUAAACAAAGCUAUAAAAAUUACAGUACCAAAGCAGUCAGACUCACAGCCUAAUUCUGAUAACCUAAGUCGCCAUGGUGAAUGUGGGAAAAAGCAAGUGUCUUACAGAACUGAUAUUGUUGGUGGCGUACCCAUCAUUACUCCCACUCAGAAAGAAGAAGUAAAUGAAUGUGGUGAAAGUAUUGACAGAAAUAAUCUGAAACGGUCACAAAGCCAUCUUCCUUACUUUACUCCUAAACCACCUCAAGAUAGUGCGGUUAUCAAAGCUGGAUAUUGUGUAAAACAAGGAGCAGUGAUGAAAAACUGGAAGAGAAGAUAUUUUCAAUUGGAUGAAAACACAAUAGGCUACUUCAAAUCUGAACUGGAAAAGGAACCUCUUCGUGUAAUACCACUUAAAGAGGUUCAUAAAGUCCAGGAAUGUAAGCAAAGCGACAUAAUGAUGAGGGACAACCUCUUUGAAAUUGUAACAACGUCUCGAACUUUCUAUGUGCAGGCUGAUAGCCCUGAAGAGAUGCACAGUUGGAUUAAAGCAGUCUCUGGCGCCAUUGUAGCACAGCGGGGUCCCGGCAGAUCUGCGUCUUCUGAGCAUCCCCCCGGUCCUUCAGAAUCCAAACACGCUUUCCGUCCUACCAACGCAGCCACCGCCACCUCACAUUCCACAGCCUCUCGCAGCAACUCUUUGGUCUCAACCUUUACCAUGGAGAAGCGAGGAUUUUACGAGUCUCUUGCCAAGGUCAAGCCAGGGAACUUCAAGGUCCAGACUGUCUCUCCAAGAGAACCAGCUUCCAAAGUGACUGAACAAGCUCUGUUAAGACCUCAAAGUAAAAAUGGCCCUCAGGAAAAAGAUUGUGACCUAGUAGACUUGGACGAUGCGAGCCUUCCGGUCAGUGACGUGUGAGGCAGAAGCGCACGGAGCCUGCCUGCCUCUGCCGUCCUCAGUUUCCUUUCAUGAGGCUUCUAGCCAAAGAUGAUAAAGGGGGAAAUGGUUUUUAGUGCGUAUAUUAUACUGCCUCUUAGGUGUACUCUUUAUAAGCUGGUAAACCAAGAAUCUAGGGAGUGGCCAAACUAAAUAUAAUUUCUUUAAAAAAGAAAGAAAAAGGAAAAAUCCAAAAUAUCUCAGUAUCAUCUGUCUGAAGCAUUGUGUGUUCUCAUUCGGGUGGUAACAAUGUAUGUGUAAUAUUUUUUUCUUAGUGAUUUUGACAGUUUAAAUGUUUAACAACUUAAAGCAUUAAAAAUGCUUAUUAAUAACUUUGGUCAUUUAAAAAAUGCUACAAUGACUUCCUAUUAAAGGUUCAAUAUUUACACAUUCUUAUUGGUUGAUAUUACCACAUGAAAUAUUGCCAGACCAAGAUACCUAAACUCAUGAUGUCUGUGGUGCUGUAAAAUUUAUACUAAAAUGUGGACUAUUUUGAAAUUAUAACCAUUUUUGAUGCCCUGAAUCUUGAGGUGACUUAUUUUGCAUAGAGGAUAUGGAUAGACCAACAGUAAGGGUUGUGGGUUAUACCGGCAUAGAGAAAAGAAGAAAACUAGAAUUGAAACAACUGUGUCUUAGACAUUUGUUUGAAAAAGCUUCAUCAGGCCUUGGAGCAGUCACUGCUUUAUUCCGCAAAAAUUAUUUGGUAGGAAAUUUUUGGGAGAUCUGAUUUUCUUAUCCAAGUUUUGUAAAUAGUUGUUAUUUCUAUAUUUGGAUUGGUGAAAGACCUCAAGUUUAUAUGUAAAGACAUAACUGCCCUUAGUCAUGAAAUUGUUGUGACCUCUACUUUUUGUCACUAAUAGCCUACAUUCAAGUGCCUGUGUUUUUUCAUCUUGUUUAGGAAUGUUUUGAGAUUAAUGUGCUUAAAAGUCCUACGUGACUGAUUUUAAACAUUGUGAUAAAAUUAAUUUUCAGUAGAAUAGUUGAAUGUGUUAAGAUAGGAUUUUAUGUUAGAGAUACCAGAAUGCUGGUAUUCUACUACUUGUGCAAUAUAUAUGUUUUAAAAAACAAAUUUGAGAAUACAUUUAAUCAUAGGGAUAUAGAUAUAAGCACCUCUCUAAAGAAUCUUUAGUUUCCGACGUUGAAUUAUAGACCAGUUUGAGUAAGUACUGCUUUUUUUUUUUGGAGACGGGCUCUCGCUCUGUUGCUCAGGCUGGAGUGCAGUGGCGUGAUCUCAGCUCACUACAGCCUCCACCUCGUGGGUUCAAACAGUUGUGCUGCCUCAGCUUCCCGAGUAGCUAGGAUUACAGGUGCAUGCCACCACACCUGGCUAAUUUUUGUAUUUUAGUAGAGAUGGGGUUUCACCAUGUUGGCCAGGCUCGUCUCGAACUCCUGACUUCAGGUGAUCCACCCAUCUCAGCCUCCCAAAGUGCUGGGAUUACAGGCGUGAGCCACCAUGCCCGGCCCAUAAGUACCGUUUUUGAGGUUCAGUCUUAAACAUUUGCUUUAAGAAAACAGUCUUGAAUUUCACAUGCUGCUAUUUUUAUAUUUUGCCAUUUUACAGUACUGUUUUGUUUUGAAUUCAUGCAUAUCAUUGAAAAUUUCUCGUUUUCAUUUUCUUAGAUGACUUCUUGUCUGAGACAGAAAAAUUUCCUACUACAGCAGUGCAGUCCAGAGGUUAAGAUGUAUUAGAAUUAUACAAUAUCAGUUUAAAAAUCUGUAUGCAUAAAGAAUGCACCACUCAACUUUUUUAUUCAUAAGCUAAUAUUUUUUUAAAGUUACAUUAAGAUUUUUUCUCUUUUGCAGCUACAUUUGAAAGUGAUAGAAUAAAGAGAUUUUAAUGAGUUAUCACUUUUUCAGCUGAUAUAUUCAUUUUAAUGGCUUUUUUGAAAGUUCCUUUUUCAUGAACACACCCGAGAAAUCUUAAAUAGACACUUUGCAAUAUUUAAGAACCUAAUGCUGUUUAAUUUUGGUACAGCUUCCACAUUGCAUGUUCACUUUAGUAUUUGCAAUUUGAUAUAUUUCAUGGUGGCAAAAUAUUAGCUCUGUUUUGGGACAUUUUAAAAUAGAACUAUCCUUGUUCGAUAGCAUAGGAAAAUGUUCUGGUGAUUGUCAGGGUCUCCUAAUAUUUAUCUCAAUUCUUUUAUAAGUCUAUGGAAAUUAUUUAAUUAUUUUAAAACGUACACACUUUUCUUGUAAAUAUGUCACAUCUGAGUUCAAAAAAAUUACUUUGAAUACCUUAAUAUUUGCUGCAUUUUUUUCCGUAUAUAUAACAUGUCUUCUUUCAGAAUGGGAAUAUAUGUGUGCCUCCCAACAUUUACUGUUAAAGUGUGUUAUCUUUAUAUGUCAAACUGGUUGAACACUGUAAUGAGAAUAAACUGCACAGAGUUUAUUCUGACUUAUUUCUCAUUUUGUUUGGUUCAGCCCUUGUGUGAUGAAGUAAAUACAAUGAUUAGGGGUGUGUUUGGUUAAUUGACUUCAGUUUACAUAUUUAAGGACAGAGUAAUUAUUUGGUCAUCUUUGCAAGAAUAAGAAACUUCAGAUCUGUGAAUUCUUAAUGCAUCCCUGCAUGUGAAAUUAUAGAAGGAAAAAUGAUUUUUUUUUGAUAGGGGAAAGAACUUGCUUAUUUUUCUUAAUUAAAAAACAUGUUCUCAAAAGCAGAAUUAUCAUAUGUUAGCCUCAGAGCAUCGUGUGGAUCAUCUGGGCUGCUCACAGUGCUCCAUGAUUAUUUAGACGGCAUGAUGUAAGGCGGAAAGCAGAGGGCAUCUUAAUCUCCGGGUGGGCAGUUGAGAUGCACUCAAAAAACUAUGUCGGGUGUUAGAGGCUGCUCCUUGCAAACGUUCCCUAUUGGUGAUAAAUAUUCCACGUCUGUUGCGGUGAACACCAUAUACAGGGCCUAGUGCAGUGCUUGGUGCACUUGGUAAAGCUUAAAUACUUCUCCAGUGAGGACAAGGCAUUACUGUAGAAUGUGUGAACUUCCCACAUUAGAGAAAAGUGUAUACCUAUUUGUUAGAUAAAUUGUACUUUUGAAUUUCUGGAAUAUUCUUUCCUUAAAGCAACUUGCCUUCAAUGAUUCGAGAUACCUUCUUUUGCUUGUUGUGUCUAAUCCAUUGUCAGAUCCUGCUGCUUUUCCCUGGCAUGUUCAUACCUUGUUCUCUGAAAUUCAGCCGGGAAUGACUUUGAACCAGUAUGUCUGCUCACCUAUUCAUGUCCUGUUGGGGCUCUCCUGGACUACCCUAUUCCUGUCAUUGUGCAGAGUAGGUAUCAAAGUAGACAUCUUCAUCUGUUGCCUUUUCCUGAAAAGCUGAAUGACGACUUAAAGAUCAGCUAGGCCAAGCCCCCACCAUCAAUGCUAACUGAGAUAAAUUGAGACCCCAGAAAGGAGGAGGAUUUGCCUGGCCCAUGGGGCACGUUAGCAACGAAGCUGUAACUGUUGGCUUCUCACUGUACUUGGGAGCAUCAUUAGGAUCUGUGCCCAGGGUGUAGCUAGAGUAAUCCAGCCAAAUAUACCAGGUUGCUUCCUAAUAACCUAUGGCAUUCCGCACCUCCUCUCCAAAACACAUAGGCUUAGUGUUCUUUUUUUUUUUCUCAGUCUUUUUCUGAAGGCCAUUUGUUGUGUGAAAUGGCUUUCUUCAUCUUAGACCUUCAGAUCUCUGUUGAAUCAAGUGACUUGUGAAUGUCUAGCCAUGCAACAGCAGCUCACGUACUUCCUGUGUGUGUUCUAAUAUGCUGCUGCUACAAAUGGAUGGAAUACAUUGUCCUAGAAUGCAAGGACCUUGAGGUUUGUGUCUGCGUUUCACCUGUUAGGUUUUCUGUAGUUCUGUUAGACGAUGGAUAUGUUUAUGUUUGAUACCCCUUUAUUGCAGCAUGUUCAGCACUUUCAAAAAGGAGAGCAUUUAGUAUUUGGUUCUAUUUAGGAAGGGCUUUUAAUUAUUUCCAAGAACUUAUCUAGGUUUAGCAAAUGAAGCUUUAAUUUUUUUAGUAUGUCCUACCUAUUUUUCUGAAAUAUUAUUUUCUUACCAAAAGUGCCAUUGCGUGUGUAAGCCAUGUUUUCUUGUUCACGCCAGCCAUGGGAGGUGAUAAUAGCCUGGGUAACAAUUUCAGUCAUACUUGUCCAGGAGCCUGCUUCCUUGAAAGUGACUGAUGUUCCGGUGUUCCUUUCUUUCCCAUUGGGUCUUGGACACCUGAUUGUUACCAUGGUGUUUGUCCACUGCUGCUAUGGUCUUGUUGAUGCUGCUCCAAAUAUGUAGCUGUGUUUUCUGGAUACAUAAUUUUUAUUUAAAGCUUAUUCCUGGACACAUUUUGUCCAUUUUUGAAAAGAUCUAAACUAAUUUGACUAGUAGAAUUAGGCUAACAAUACAUGGUUCAAGGAAAAAUACUGCCUUUUGUAAUAAAAGUUUCUUCUUGCCUAGUGUCUCAUUGGUCUGAAUAUAAUGGCUGUCUUAGACCCGGCAUCCUGGCGCCUGUCUUCAACUCUAGUUCUGCCGUAUGUGACUUUAGGCAAGUGUGUGUGUUUCGGAACUUCAUUUUCUACAUUAUAUAAAAUGGAAUUGGAUAAAAGCUACAUCUGUCUUGGUAAUUAUUAUUAUUAACUGAUGCAACUUUUUUUCCUUUGAAAAGUAUUUUUUUUAUUAUUUAAGUUUUAGGGUACAUGUGCACAAUGUGCAGGUUAGUUACAUAUGUAUACAUGUGCCAUGCUGGUGUGCUGCACCCAUUAACUCGUCAUUUAGCAUUAGGUAUAUCUCCUAAUGCUAUCCCUCCCCCCUCCCCCCACCCCCCAACAGUCCCCAGAGUGUGAUGUUCCCCUUCCUGUGUCCAUGUGUUCUCAUUGUUCAAUUCCCAUCUAUGAGUGAGAACAUGCGGUGUUUGGUUUUUUGUCCUUGCGAUAGUUUACUGAGAAUGAUGAUUUCCAAUUUCAUCCAUGUCCCUACAAAGGACAUGAACUCAUCAUUUUUUAUGGCUGCAUAGUAUUCCAUGGUGUAUAUGUGCCACAUUUUCUUAAUCCAGUCGAUCAUUGUUGGACAUUUGGGAAAAGUAUUUUUAAUGUUUUUAUCCUAAACCCAAAAUAAGAAGGGAAAGCUGUAAACAUUUUUGCUUUAACAAAAAGGAAAUCCCUUUCUUAGCUUUUCUUUCACUUCUAGUUGCAGUUCAGGAAUUUUCUGUAAGUGGUGCUUGUACCUUUAUCAAAAGUUCUGUUAACAGUUGGUGAGGCAAGAAAUAUUUGUAUCAAAAAUGCAAAGAUAUGACAGCUUAAUACCAGAUCUCAGUGUUCAGAAGUUUAGUCCAUAUAGGAUUUGUGUAUGUUAUCUAUUUUUUAAAUGAUUAAAUUGUAUGUUUUAAACCUCAAGUAAGACACAUGUUGAAAAUAUGGCUGAAUUGAGGCUAGCAUUUACAGUUUUGAUUGAUGAAAUCUGUAUUUUUUGAUACAUUUAAUAGUGCCUUACUGUGGUAUAUUCAUGUGGUAAUAGCGCCACCUUCUGGUUAUAUCAUUGCUAAAUUUAAAAUUUGGAAAUUUGGAGUCUGUUUAUUGCCUCCAUCGUAGAAAAUUAGAUAAGAUAUGUGAUUGCCUAGGAUAGUUUUGAAAUUAAUAUAAAAUUCAAACUAACAUUUACAAAUUAUAAAUUUUUUAUUUAGAGAUGAUUGUAGGUUCACAUAUAGUUGUAAGAAAUAAAACUUUCCAAACUUUCAAAAUGGGGAAUAUUUAGUAUUUGGUCCUAUUUGGAAAGAGCUUUAAUUAUUUCCAAGAACUUACCUGGGUUUAGAAAAUGAAGUUUUGGUUUUUUAAUUAUGUCCUACCUGUCAAUUUCUGUUUCUGUAAGAAAUAAUGUAGACCCACACGCCUGUAGUCCCAGCUAUUCAGGAAGCUGAGGCAAUUGGAACACUUGAGCUUAGGGGUUUGAGAUCAGCCUGGGCAGAAUAAUGAGACACCAUCUCAAAAAAAAAAAAAGAAAAGAAAAAGAUAUUGUGUACCCUUUACUCAGUUUCCCCCCAACAGCAUCUUGAAAAACUAAUACAAUAUUAUAACCAAGAUACUGACACUGAUACAGUCAAGAUGCAGAACAGUUCCAUCAUCACAAAGGCCCCUCUUUGUUGUUCUUUUUAUAGUCACAUCCAUCUCCUAUUCUGCAGGUUUGGAAGCAGACUUAGCCACUUGUCCAGAGUCAGAUUAGGCUUGAAAUGUAUCUUUCUGAUACCAAAGUUUGGGCUCUUAACACACUACUUCUACUGUCUCAGUAGAAGUCUUGAAAACUUCUCUUUUAAAAUAGUACUUCCAGAUUACUAAAUGAGUUGAAUUCAGUCUGUUUUCAACAUUUCUAGAACCAUACUAUUUCAAAUGACAUAUUAUUUAUACAUACCUUUAAAUUUAACAUUUGAGAAUCAAUCAUAGGUACGUAUCAAAUUACAACUUCCCUGAAAGAUUUCAAGCCCUGACAUUUGAUAAAUAAGGUUACCAGAAUAAAUAGUAAGUAACAGAUUGAAAUAGCUUUAAGAUGCUGGAUUCUUGCUUUGGAAACAGCUAUAGGGCCUGGUUAUAAAGAUAAUCACUUGGUAUAGGCUAACAGGUUUUUUCCAUGUGGAGAAGCUUUGACCUGAUGGAGUUGGGUCAAUUGGUGUCUUCAGUGUACGACAUGCAGCACACAGGAGACCUAAGAAGACGACAAAGAUGUCCACGAGGAAUCUGCCGAAAGAAAAUAUAAAGUAAUAUGUGAUAAAAUCUAGCAUGGAAAACUACGCAUCAGAGACUGAGAUGGCCCAUGGGUGAUGGUGUGGGUAAGAUAAGUGUUGUGAUGGAGAGGGCCUUUGGGGGGUCCCAUGAGAGAAAAAGGUACUUCUAAGUAAAAGCCAUGUGACUUUAUAAAUUUCUAAAUGUUGAUUCAGGGGUCCUAAGUGAUGGAGAAAGUUUACAUUGUUCUCUUAAGGCUCCAUUGCCUCUUUCCCUCCCGAACUGUGGUAUGUAUACCUCUAAUGCACGUUUUCUUUAGUGGGGAGGAAAGGAGGGGCUGUGGAGAACUUUCCAUGGUCAGGAACUUACAUCAGCCUUUUUUUUUUUUUUUUUUUUGCCUGUCUUUGGUACCUUAUCUUCAUGUUAUGAAUGUAACCUAUUCCCUGUGGAAACAUUUAUUAUUAUUUCCAAAUAGGGCCUUUGGUCCCAAUGGCGUCUGUUUCUUUUUGACUUCUACAUACGUCAUGCUCACGGUCUUGGUUCGUAUUGUCACUCAUGCCAUUUUUUCUUCCCAUUUGCUUUUUGCCUGUCUAGUUUGAAGGUGGAAGAUUUUCCGAUGAAUCAGAUAUGGCAAGUGAAAGGAAGUGAAGAAUUAAGGGUAAUGACAAGGUUUUCAGCCCGAACAACUAGAAGCCAUGAACUGAGGUAGCAAAGAUUGCAGGUAGAGCAGGUUUGAUGGAAAAGAUCAUGAUUGCAGUAUUGGUUGCAGUAUUGAGUGUUAGGGUUGACAUGUCAGACAUCCAAGUAGAAAUGGCAGGCAGGCAGUUGGAUAUGCAAAUUUGGAAUUGAGAGAAAUCAUUAUUGGAAAUAAAAAUGUGGGAGUCUUCAAAGUAUUCGGUGCUAUUGAAGGCUUUGAAACUGGAUGAGAUCAUCUUUAGAGAGAAUGAAGAUGAAAGAAGAAAAGAGAACCAUGGAAUGAGCCCUGGGGCGCUCCAAUAUUAAGAGCUUUGGAAGAAGAGGAGGAAGUAGCCAUGAUGAAUGAGAAGGUGUGACCACCACAUCAACAGGAUAUCAAGAGUACGUUGUGUCUUAGAAGCCAAGUGAAGAAAAUGAAGUGAGGAGGAGAUCGGAUGUUUCAAAUUCUGCUCGCAGGUCAAGUUAAGAGGCAGCCUGAGAAAUGCCCUUUGUGUUUGGCAACGUGGACAGUACAGAUGUCAUUGGUGAUCUUGCCAGGGCCUGUUCUGAUGGAGUGGUGGGGACAAAUAGAACUCUUUUUGAGGCAUUUUGCUGCAAGAGGACUGGAGAAAGGUGACGGUUGCUAGUAGCAAAAGUAGUCUUUUCUUCUUAAGACAGUGGCUUGGCCAGACACGGUGGUUCACGCCUGUAAUCCCAGUUUUGGAGGUCUAGGUGGGAGAAUAGCUUGAAUCUAGGAGUUCAAGACCAUCCUGGGCAACAUGGCAAAAUCCCAUUUCUACAAAAAAUACAAAAAUUAGCAGGGUGUGGUGGCGUGCAUCUGUAGUCCCAGCUACUUGGGAGGCUGAGGCGGGAGGAUCACCUGAGCCUGGGGAGGUUGAGGCCACAGUGAGCUGUGAUUGUGCCACUGCACUCUAGCCUGGGUGAUAGAGUGAGUCACUGUCUCAAAAAACAAACAGAAAACAAUAACAAAAGAUGGUGGCUUAUUUGUUGAUGAAAUGACCCAGUAGGAAAAGAAAGAUUGAUGAUGUAGAAGAGUACAGAAUUGUUGGAACAAGUCCUUGAGGAGGUGAGAUGAGAUGGAAGCUAGGGCACAAGUUGGCUUGACUUCUUCAAAUGCACAGGUGUUUAUCUGGGGUAGGAAGGCACAGUAUGUGGUGCAGCCACUGGUUAAGUGGGUAGACGUGGAGGGGUAAGUCUCUGAAAGUCUCUGCCUUAGUCUCAGUAAACUAGGAAACAAAAUUCGCAACUGCAAGUAAGGUGGGGAAAGGUGUGAAAGGCAUGAGAGAAUAGAUGUCUAGGAUUGGGGAGAAGGAAUGGACUAGGGACAUUUAGGAUAUUCUGAGCAGCACUGAAAACCCACUGAGCUCUGUGUGCAUGAAUGACAGUGUUCAAUAACUGAUAACUGUAGUCAUUUUUGUCACGCUCCUGACUUCAGUGGAAAAGCCUCUAGUGCAGGCAUGUCCAAUCUUUUGGCUUCCCUGGGCCCCAGUGGAAGAAGAAGAAUUGUCUUGGGUCAUACAUGAAAUACACUAACAUUAAUGAUAGCUGAUGAGCUAAAAAAAAAAAAAUCGCAAAAAAAUCUCAUAAUGUUUUUAAGAAAGUUUACAAAUCUGUGUUGGGCCGCAUUCAAAGCCGUCCUGGGCCACAUGCGGCCCGUGGGCUGUGGGUUGGACAAGCUUGCUCUAGUGGUUCCCCAUGCUGCUGGCUUUUGGGCUGAGAAAUAUUUUAUCAGGUUAAAGAAGUAUCCAACUAUUCAUAUUUUGUUGAGUUUUUUUCUUAAGAAUGGUGAUUGAAUUUUGUUAAAUAUCUUCAAUAUGUCUGGAAAUAAUAUUUUUAUCCCUCUUUAAUUUGGUGAAAGCUGUUAAUCCAGUUCUCAAUAUUUAACCAUCAUUACAUUUCUGGAAUAAAUCCCAUUUGGUCAAGAUAUGUUAUUUUAAAAAUCUGCUAGAUUUUGUUUGCUAUUAGGGAUUUUUGCAUAAAUAUAAAUGAUACUGGUCUGCAUUUUUCUUUUGUGUAGCUCUAGUCUUUGUAGGUUUUGUGGUGUUUUACUAGCUUCAUAGAAAAUACUUGAAAGGUUUUUUUUUUUUUUUAAAUUUUAAGCUGUUACAGAACAGCUUCAAAAGAAUUGGUAUUCUAGGCUGGGCACAGUGGCUCACGCCUGUAAUCCUAGCAUUUUGGGAGGCCAAGGCAUUUCUCAGGCUGGAUCACCUGAGGUCAGGAGUUCGAGACUAGCCUGCUCAACAUGGCGAAACCCUGUCUCUACUAAAAAUACAAAAAAUUAGCCAGGCAUGGUGGCAGGUGCCUGUAAUCCCAGCUACGUGGGAGGCUGAGGCAGGAGAAUUGCUUGAACCCGGGAGGCAGAGGUUGCAGUAAGCUGAGAUGGUGCCACUACACUCCAGCCUGGGUGACAAGAGUGAAACUCCAUCUCAAAAAAAAAAAGUUGGUAUUCUAUACUCCUUAAAGAGUUAGUGGACUUCCGCUAGGAAAUCCUCUCAACCUGGUGCUCUUUUGAGGGUGUGCCAUUGACAACCUCCUCAUUUCCUCUAUGAGAAUUGAUAUGCUUAGGCUUUCUAUCUUUUCUGGGGUCAGUUUUGAUCAAUUAUAUCCAUAGAAAAUUAUACAUUUUAUCUAAGUUUUUAAAUGUAUUUGCAUGGAGCUGAGCACAAUAUACAGAACUUAUUUAAGGAGAAAUGCAUUACUGCAGAUCCCACUUUGUUCUUCAACUCAAAAUAUCCAAUGCUGUGAAGAUUGCUUAUAUGACAAGUUGUGCUAUCUUCUGAUUUUUACCUGGAAGCAAUGUGAUCACAAACAUACCACCAGAUUAAAGUGGUAGUACUCAGGUAACAGGAGGCCAUCCAAAUUAAAUUUAGGAGUCUUUAAAAAAUUAUCAAAAUUCAAUGUAAAAAGUAUAAUUUCUUGUAAAGAACAUGUGGUUCCUGGAGAACAUGUCUAGGUUCCCCAUUUGAGAAACACUGUCCUAGUGAAUAGCAUUUGAACUUAUCCUACGUUCAUUGCCCUUCCAUGUCCACCUUCUCACACAGUGCUUCUGUGUAUAUCUGGCACUCCAGUUCAACUGAACCUUUCCAUCUCCCUGUUUCCCACCUUCCUGCUAUUAUUUGUGCUGUUUCUUCUGCCUGGAACGCCACUUUCCUAAUAAUUGUUGCCUGUUAAUUCCACACCUUCAAUUCUCACCAAAAUGCCACUUUCUCCUUGAAGUGUUGGAAUUGCUUUCUCAUCUUUCCCAUCACACAAGCCUUGGUGACCCCAAAACACUGGAUUCCCUUCUCCCUUCCCAUGCCAACGUUCAGUACAGUUCAUUGGAACAGAAUUCACUUUAAGCUUUGCUCUUAAACUUUGGCCUAGUAAAUAGCUUUUCUCCUUUCACUGUAGUCCCUUUUAAAAGCCAAAGACUUCAAAAUUUGGAAGAGAUUAGAAAAUGAAAACAGUCCAAAUCCAGCUCUUUGUUGAUUAGAUUGGCCCAAAGGGGACAUAAAUAAGACAAGCAAAAUGCAAACGAAUUCUAGUAGUAAUGGCCACUGUAUAAGCACUGCACCAGUGCAGUGGUUUCAGCAGCUGGUCCUGGGCCCCUUUCAUACUUAAUGUAUGUUUGGUUUUACGUUUAAUUUUAGGUGCUAACAAUUACCUCAUGGGCCCCUCUUAAGUCUGCUGUGAGAGAAAUCCUAAUCCCCUAAGGCAGUGGUUCUCAAAGUGUGGUCCCUGAGACCAACAAUGUCAACAUUACUGAGAACUUGCUAGAAGUGCAAAUUAUUGCUCCCAUCCCAGUCCUACUGAAUCAGAUUUUCUGGGAUUAGGGCAGGCAAUCUGUUUUAACAAGGCCUACAGGUGAUUCUGACAUCCAUUAAAGUUUGAGAUCGGCUGGGCAUGGUUGCUCACACCUAUAAUCGCAGCACUUUGGGAAGCCGAGGCGAGAAGAUUGCUUGAGUUCAGGAGUUCGAGAUGAGCCUAGGUAACAUAGUGAGACAUCGUCUCUACUAAAAUUCAAAAAGAAUUAGGCAUGGUGGUGUGUGUCUGUAGUCCCAGCGACUUGCAUUGCGUGCUGAGGUGAGAGGAUCGCUUGAGCCUGGGAGAUCAAGGCUGCAGUGAGCCCUGAGUGUCACUGCACUCCAGCCUGGGCAACAGAGUGAGACCCUGUCUCAAAAAAAAAAAAAGUUUGAGAUCCUCUGCCCUAAGAUAUCCAUUAUCCAUUACAUGUAAGGAAUUAACUUCUCUCCUAUGCGACCAGGAUGGCCUUUGUUACAUAGUAUCCUUAGAGCUGAGAAAACAGUUACCUAAAUCACUGCCUGUGUUCUGUGGUUCAGAUAAAGAACCCACUGAAAGAGGCUGCGUGCAUGAACCGGCUCUGACCAACUGAACAUGAAACACAGGUUGGAAUAAAAAUAUUUUUUUAUUUGAUGGUCUUCCAUAUAGACAGAAUUUCAUCAGGAAUCAAAGAAAGGUGGUUACCACAUAUAAACACCAACUAAACUCUGAGCUUUCUGGCAACUGAAAAGGAAAACGUUGAGUUCUAGAAUAGCCUUUGUUGUUUGAUGCAACUAACCAUAUCACCUUUUAGAGCUAGAGAACCGUCCAGGUAUUAAAUGUUUGGAAUCUUUUAUGAUGUGGAUUGUGCUACAGGGGACACUGAGUAACGUGGGGACCAAUGUCCUUCACAGUUUUUGUAGAAAAAUUUUUAGGUGGUCUUCCAUAUUCACCCUUAGAAGCAAGGACAACCCUUCGAGUGUAAUUCCGUGGAGAUGAUUUCCUUCUGACUCAAACACCCAUAGCUUCCCUGUCUGUCCAUUUCGUGAGCUCCUCAUUACCUUCCAUGACUCACUUUUCCAUGUGACACGGAGCCUCCCUGGCUUCCACUGCUGAUACUGACCAUUCCUUUCUUUGUUCUCUAUGCUGCCGUGGACACAGAGCCACCAUCGCUGUUAACUGUACUAGAGUCUUUACUUUUUUUUUCUUUUGUGAGCCUAAGCCUUCCUCAAGACAAGAAUCUUUGUUUUGUUUAAAAAAAGAAUAGCCUUAAUGUUUUUUUUUCUGAUUUUAAAGUGAACACCCUAUUGUAGAACAUCCAUGUAAGCAAAAAGAAAAAAAAUAAAAAUGAUUUGUAAUUUCUCCAAGAAAUGACCUGUGUUGACAUUUCAGUGAUUAUACUUCCAAGUCUUUUACUAAAUGUGUACGUAAAUAGCUUUAUUUUUGUGUGUGUAAAAAUCUGUAGCCUCUGUAAACAAGCCAAAUGUCAUAUACACCCCACACAAAACAAUAAAAGCAAAAAUCACCA